AGAUCCGAGGACAUGUUGACGUCGUCCGAGAGUCUUAAAAUCCUGCUCUGGCCGGAUUCCAGACUCGUGGGGGAAAGGCUGGAUUUCAACAGAUCACAUGGAUCAAGGCCUUAGGGAGGUGGUUGGGGAUUCACGUAUGCCCUGGACCAUCUGGAGCCCAAGUUGCUGCAGAUCCUGUCACCACGAGUGGACACCCUCUGGCCACCAUAGCAAAGAAGUCUGCAGGCAGGAGAUGGAGUCUCGCUCUGUUGCCUAGGCUGGAGUGCAGUGGCACGAUCUCAGCUCACUGCAACCUCUGCCUUCCCAGUUCAAGCAAUUCUCCUGCCUCAGCCUCCCAGGUAGCUGGGAUUACAGUUUCCAAGGCAGGAAAGGUAAAGAGACAAAGAAAGUGCCUUGUACAGAUGCAAACGGAGGUGUAGACUGUGCAGCUGCCAAAGUGGUGACAAGCAAUCCAGAGGACCAUGAAAGGAUCUUAAUGCAAGUCAUGAACUUGAAUGUGCCGAUGAGGCCUGGCAUUCUUGUCCAGAGACAGAGUAAGGAAGUGUUGGCCACACCCUUAGAAAACAGAAGGGACAUGGAGGCAGAAGAGGAGAACCAAAUAAAUGAGAAGCAAGAGCCUGAGAAUGCUGGAGAAACUGGUCAAGAAGAGGAUGAUGGUUUGCAGAAAAUACACACAUCUGUCACUAGAACUCCUUCAGUUGUUGAAAGCCAAAAAAGACCUUUAAAAGGAGUGACAUUUUCUAGGGAGGUAAUUGUUGUGGAUCUUGGGAAUGAAUACCCUACACCUCGAAGCUAUACUCGAGAACAUAAAGAGAGGAAAUGAAGCUCAAAAAAGGGUAAGAGUGAAAGAAAAUGUAACGUUUGACUAACGUUGAAAGACUGAGGGUACAAAAUCAUGUUGAAACAACAAAACAAUGGGGAAUUAAGCAAAUAAAGAUAUUAUUUUACCUUUGUGCAGAAAGGAGUGAGCCAUGUGCAAAAUUCUGUAAGUAAAAUACUUAGAGCUUGAAUAUAAUUUUUUAAAAAUUCAAAUCUGAGUUCAAGAAAUUGAUUGUAUUGCCCUUAAAACUAUCUACUCAAACACUGUUCUGGCAUGUGAAUAAAGUGAUUUUUGUUUGUACAAA